GUCUAGAGCUCCGGGCGCGGGGAGGCGCGGCCAUGGCAGCUCCGGAGCCGCUGUCCCCGGCGGGCGGUGCGGGCGAGGAGGCGCCGGAGGAGGACGAGGACGAAGCGGAGGCCGAGGACCCUGAGCGGCCGAAUGCGGGAGCGGGCGGUGGACGCAGUGGCGGCGGCGGCAGUAGCGUCAGCGGAGGAGGCGGCGGCGGCGGGGCCGGGGCGGGGGGCUGCGGCGGGCCCGGGGGCGCGCUCACCAGGCGCGCGGUCACACUGCGGGUGCUCCUCAAAGACGCGCUGCUGGAGCCUGGCGCCGGGGUGCUGUCCAUCUACUACCUGGGGAAGAAGUUCCUGGGCGACCUGCAGCCAGACGGAAGGAUCAUGUGGCAGGAGACCGGGCAGACCUUCAACUCACCCAGCGCCUGGGCCACCCACUGCAAGAAGCUGGUGAACCCUGCCAAGAAGUCGGGCUGUGGCUGGGCCUCUGUCAAGUACAAAGGCCAGAAACUGGACAAGUACAAGGCCACCUGGCUCCGGCUGCACCAGCUGCACACGCCUGCCACGGCUGCUGAUGAGAGCCCAGCCAGUGAAGGGGAGGAGGAGGAGUUGCUGAUGGAAGAGGAGGAGGAGGACGUUCUGGCAGGGGUCUCAGCAGAGGACAAGAGUCGGAGACCACUGGGGAAGAGCCCUUCAGAGCCUGCCCACCCGGAGGCCACAACCCCAGGGAAGCGGGUGGACAGCAAGAUCCGGGUUCCGGUCCGCUACUGCAUGCUGGGCAGCCGCGACUUGGCCAGGAACCCCCACACCCUGGUGGAAGUAACAUCCUUUGCAGCCAUCAACAAGUUCCAGCCGUUCAACGUGGCUGUUUCUAGCAACGUGCUGUUCCUGCUGGACUUCCACAGUCACCUGACACGGAGUGAGGUCGUGGGUUACCUGGGGGGCCGCUGGGACGUCAACAGCCAGAUGCUGACGGUGCUCAGAGCCUUCCCUUGUCGGAGCCGGCUCGGGGACGCAGAGACUGCAGCUGCCAUCGAAGAGGAGAUCUACCAGAGCCUGUUCCUGCGGGGCCUGUCCCUGGUGGGCUGGUACCACAGCCACCCACACAGCCCGGCGCUGCCAUCUCUGCAGGACAUCGACGCACAGAUGGACUACCAGCUGCGGCUGCAGGGCUCCAGCAAUGGCUUCCAGCCCUGCCUCGCCCUGCUCUGCUCCCCUUACUAUUCUGGCAACCCAGGCCCCGAGUCCAAGAUCUCACCUUUCUGGGUGAUGCCUCCUCCCGAGCAAAGGCCCAGUGACUAUGGCAUCCCCAUGGAUGUGGAGAUGGCCUACGUCCAGGACAGCUUCCUGACCAAUGACAUCCUUCACGAGAUGAUGCUGCUGGUGGAGUUCUACAAGGGUUCCCCUGACCUCGUGAGGCUCCAGGAACCCUGGAGCCAGGAGCACACCUACCUCGACAAGCUUAAGAUCUCCUUGGCCAGCAGGACGCCCAAGGACCAGAGCCUGUGUCACGUCCUGGAACAGGUGUGCGGCGUCCUCAAGCAGGGGAGCUGAGCCUUCCAGGGCAGGGUGGGCUCCAGUUGUCUUGAGGGUCCGGAUGGGCUCAGGUAAUAAAGAAACGGAAGCAGCA